GAGCUGUUGCGGGGCUUGCUGGGAUCAUGGCGGAGAAUCACUGCGAGCUCCUGUCGCCGGCCCGGGGCGGCAUCGGGGCGGGGCUGGGGGGCGGCCUGUGCCGCCGCUGCAGCGCUGGGCUCGGCGCCCUGGCCCAGCGCCCUGGCAGCGUGUCCAAGUGGGUCCGACUCAACGUCGGCGGCACCUACUUCCUCACCACUCGGCAGACCCUGUGCCGGGACCCGAAAUCCUUCCUGUACCGCUUAUGCCAGGCCGAUCCCGACCUGGACUCAGACAAGGAUGAAACAGGCGCCUAUUUAAUCGACAGAGACCCCACCUACUUUGGGCCUGUGCUGAACUACCUGAGACACGGCAAGCUGGUGAUUAACAAAGACCUCGCGGAGGAAGGAGUGUUGGAGGAAGCAGAAUUUUACAAUAUCACCUCAUUAAUAAAACUUGUAAAGGACAAAAUUAGAGAACGAGACAGCAAAACAUCGCAGGUGCCUGUGAAGCAUGUGUACCGUGUGCUGCAGUGCCAGGAGGAGGAGCUCACGCAGAUGGUGUCCACCAUGUCCGACGGCUGGAAGUUCGAGCAGUUGGUCAGCAUCGGCUCCUCUUACAACUAUGGGAACGAAGACCAAGCCGAGUUCCUCUGUGUGGUGUCCAAGGAGCUGCACAACACCCCGUACGGUACGGCCAGCGAGCCCAGCGAGAAGGCCAAGAUUUUGCAAGAACGAGGCUCAAGGAUGUGAGGGACACAGUAUUGACAGCUGAAGAAAUGAUUUACGUUUUCCCGAGAUGUAAUGAACUGCCAUGUCCAGGAAGCUUGGCUGUGAGAAGAAACCUGCUUUUGAUCAUUUUUCUAGAGAUCUGGGUGUGAAUCCUUUUUUGCCUCUGAGGUGGGUGGUGAGAGACGGGCCCAGCUGUCCAAGGCCAGACGUCCCCAAGUUGGGGGAGCACGGCGGCCGGGUGGGCGCUGCCUCUUGGGGGGGCCUCGCUCUGUUUUUUCCAAGUGCCACGUGGGACUGAGGCAGACACUCCCAGUCAGCCCGCUCGAUCCUGAAGAUCGUGUGAAGGAAGCGUUCUUGGUGCUACACACAGUCUGGAAAAGCAGCCUGGGCUUCACUGGCAGGAAGCGGCCGCAGCCGCGUCAGUGUCCAGCACGUCGUGGCCUCUGGUCCGACCACCAGGCCCUAGUCUCGGUCAGGGAGUCUGCUCUGCCUCCCAGGCGGGAUCGCUGGUUUCUCUCGACCUCGCAGAGCUCCUGACAAAGGCGGCUUCUGCGUCGUCACUGCUUCCCGGCGCCAUUCCGAGGCCGGGCCUUCUUCUGACACGGGCUCCAACCCCACCUGACCAAGCCCGGGACAGUCAAGGCUUCUCAAUUUGUAUUUUCCAGGCAAGAGAACUUUGUACCCCUUCUCUGUGUGGAUAGACUCCCCAGCGUUUUUCCUCUGGAAAUGCCCACAGGGCUUGCCGCGUGGAGACUGAUCUGUUCCAUCCGUUAGCGCGAGGUAGCAGUGUCGCCUCGCCCCUCCCACUGCGGGCUCACGGGGAGCUGGCGUCUGUCAGUGCCUUGUCACGCCUGGCAUAGAGGUUGGGCUGGAGGCCUGUCCACUGGCUUCUGGAGCUGAAGGUCUGCGUCACGGUGAAAAUUCGGGAUGUUUACAGAGCAUCACAAAUGCCUCUCUCUCGCCGCUCUCUCAUUUUCUUUGUAUAACUAUGCAGCCUUCCCUCUCUUUCUGGGAUGUUUGGGACUUCACUCGACCUGCACGGGCUCUGCCCGACAUGCCGUGGGAGCUGCUGGGAUUCCUUUAGAAACCGCUGCCCGCAUGCUUUGAAAACAGACCUUUCUCAGCUGGCUGUGGGGACCUGUCAGAGUCUGGGGACUCGGCGUGCAGGGCGGGCUCCAAGCGCUUUGCUUCCGGAACUCCGGCUUCCCAAGGGGUACUGUGCAGACUGACCACCGGCCUCCCGCCUGCAGGUCAGAGGCUCUGACACUGUCUGGUUUCCAAUGCUUCUGGAGACUUCCUGCCUAGGCCUCAUCCUCCUCUUUGCCAGUCACCUGAUUAACCAAUUCUCCAGCAUUAGGACUUACCUCCUUCUUUUUGUAAGGUCUCUUGUAUGUUGUUAAAUGUUUGGCUUAAACAAUUUAUAAAAGCCUUUCUAGAAGGCAGACUUAGCCCCAGCAGAGCCUGGGAGGAAGGCGGCCGCUGGGGCUCCUGGGCAUCCUCUCUGGGGAGCUGCUGGCCGCUUAGCGUUGUUUGAUUUUUGACCUUGACAUAGUAGAUAGGCUUGUGGUUUUUUUAAUUUAAAGAUAUUAAGACUUAAUUCACUAAAAUUUAUUCUAAGGGGAUAUUUAUACUUUUAUACUUUUUUAGGUAUCGUAUUUUAUCAGCUUACAGUUUAAUGCCUAAGUUUCCCCUGGAAAUAGCAAAUAAAAUUGUGUAUUUAUGAA